GGCUGGACGCAGCCGGGUUUGUCCGGAGCGCUCUCCAGAUGCGGGCUCCACUGUUGGAUGUAUAGUCUUGUGAAGACAUUGUGACAUCACUGGACUGGUCUGAUCUGCAAAAUAUGAAGCGGCCACUGAGCCCACCCCCACCGGCUGAGAAGGAGACCCCCAUAUCUGGAGCUGCUGAGUGCCUCCCUCGGCCCCCAGAACCACCUAAGCCCAAGCGAGAAAGAAAGCGGCCAUCGUACACGCUCUGUGAUGUCUGCAACAUCCAGCUGAACUCGGCGGCCCAGGCCCAGGUGCACUGUGGGGGGCGGGCCCACCAGAGGCGGCUUCGGCAGCUCAGCUUGGGGAAGAGCCCCUCAGGGCCAGCAGGCCCGGCCUCCGGCGCCCCCAGCCCCCUGCUGGCCUCCCUGCCCCUGCCCACCCGGCCUCUGCAGCCCCCGCUGGACUUCAAGCACUUGCUCGCCUUCCACUUCAAUGGCGCUGCCCCGCUCAGUCUCUUCCCCAACUUCAGCACGAUGGACCCGGUCCAGAAAGCUGUCAUCAGCCACACGUUUGGUGUCCCCUCCCCUCUGAAGAAGAAGCUGUUCAUUUCCUGUAACAUCUGUCACCUGAGGUUCAACUCAGCGAACCAGGCCGAGGCACAUUAUAAAGGCCACAAACACGCCAGAAAACUCAAGGCUGUCGAGGCUGCCAAGAGCAAGCAGAGGCCACACACCCAGGCCCAGGAUGGGGCUGUAGUGUCCCCAAUCCCAACGCUGGCCAGUGGAGCCCCUGGAGAGCCACAGAGUAAAGUUCCUGCAGCCCCUCCUCUUGGGCCUCCACUCCAGCCACCACCAACUCCAGACCCUACAUGCAGGGAGCCAGCCCACUCAGAGCUCUUGGAUGCUGCCUCCUCAUCCUCUUCUUCCUCCUGCCCACCUUGCUCCCCAGAGCCUGGGAGAGAGGCACCGGGGCCUGAGCCAGCGGCAGCUGCCGUGGGAAGCAGCAUGAGUGGGGAAGGCAGGAGUGAGAAGGGGCACCUCUACUGCCCCACGUGUAAGGUGACAGUGAACUCGGCCUCCCAGCUUCAGGCUCACAACACAGGAGCCAAGCACCGGUGGAUGAUGGAAGGUCAGCGAGGGGCUCCCCGGAGGAGCCGGGGCCGCCCGGUGUCCAGGGGAGGUGCCGGACACAAAGCCAAGAGAGUCACAGGGGGCCGGGGCGGCCGGCAGGGGCCCAGCCCUGCCUUCCACUGUGCUCUCUGUCAGCUCCAGGUCAAUUCAGAGACCCAACUGAAGCAGCACAUGAGCAGCAGGAGGCACAAAGACCGCCUGGCCGGGAAGACCCCCAAGCCCUCCAGCCAGCACAGCAAGCUGCAGAAGCACGCAGCGCUGGCUUCUAAACUGGCCUUGCAGAAGCAACUCACCAAGACGUUGGCAGCCCGCUUCCUGCCCAGCCCGCUCCCCACCGCAGCCACUGCCAUCUGUGCUCUGCCAGGGCCCCUGGCCCUCCGCCCUGCCCCUACAGCAGCCACUACCCUCUUCCCGGCUCCCAUCCUGGGCCCAGCUCUGUUUCGCACCCCAGCAGGAGCUGUCCGCCCUGCCACAGGACCUAUCGUCCUUGCCCCUUAUUAGCCCUCAUGGGGAGGCCAGAGCUGAUUUCCCAAUAGCCACUCCUUGUCUCCUCCUGUCCUGAGACACCUUGGUUUCCUACAUGCCACAGGGACUGUGAACAGCUUCAGGGGUCCUGCCCGAUCCAGAAAGAGCUGGGCUAGUUUUAAGGGCAGCUGCCUUCCAAGGACUGUCCCCACCCUCCUUUCGCAGGCCUUCCAGGGUUAAUCCUAGGCUUGCCUGCAUUUCCCACCCUGACAGACCCCAAAGAUCUAUGCAAAAUCUCAGCCCCAGCCAUGUGGUGCUCUCACUUUCCUCCACCCAAGACCCACAUGGCCAGACUCUAGGAAUCUUAGCUUCUACAAGCCAUCCUCUCCUAGCCAGGGGACGACUCUCUGACCUCUAUUCCUAGGCUUUGGGGCUUCACUGGAGAUAGGGAUGGGGUCUCUAGCUGCAGCAGGCUCAAGGCUGUCAGGACAAGGUGACCAUGGGAGUGUGACAGAGGACCAUGGAGGAGAAAGGGGGACCCAAAAGUCCUUCGAUCAGCAGUGCUAAGGUGGGGCAGAGCCAAGGAGGUAGUGGGGCUGGUUCUGAAAGCUUUUGGGGGCUUCAUCUGCUCUGAAGGGGUGGGACUAAGAGAGGAGGUGAUGUUCUGGUUGGGCCCAGGGUUUUGUUUUAAUCUUAAGUCUUCUGGGCAUUCAUGGGCCCAGUCUUUUUUUCUGUCUGAGAGUAUCAUUCUGUUGCCCAGGUUAGAGUGCAGUGGUGCAAUCUUGGCUCACUGCAUGCAGCCUCUGCCUCCCUGGUUCAAGUGAUACUUGCUGAUAAGCCCAGUCUUAAUAUUGAGGGAGUAACUCAUCCCUCAGAAGCUCUUCUUCUUAGCCUUUCUCUGACUUCCUGAACCCCAACUCUUGGAGGGCGGGUGUGGGUCUCCCUCAGACUAUGGACUCAGCUAACACCGAACCCCCCGCAGAGCUCCCAAAGGAAGAGCUUUCCCCUACAGCUUCCCACUCCAAACUGGUCCUAGCACUAAAUUCAGCUUUCCCUUCUCCCAACCAGCCCCUGCCACUGUGAAGCUGAGUGUUGGGAGGCAGUCUCACAUGCACUGGCAAGACCCAUUUUCAUGCUGUCAAUGUCAAUGUCACAAACUCCUUUCCACUGCAGCACUGCCCCCUCCCCACCCCACAAUAUGGGACCCUGCCAGUAUCCCCCUGUAUCUUUUUUUUGUUUUUUAAAGACAUUUCCAAUGGGAGAACCAGAAAAAGGGGGAGGGGAGGGAAACUUUUUGAUAACAAUUGUGGUUUUAUUGUGUCCAACCAAUGCAUCAAUAAAUGAACUUGAAGCCCAA